ACUGUGAGGGAGGACCCCUGUGCCAUGCCCCUGUCACCCCAGUGUUUCUCCUUUGUCCACACAGCGGUCUGGGUUAGAAACACCAGGGCCCACUGCAACUUUUGUUAGGGCCACUUAGUGCUGGUUGGGAGCCACAGGGCCGUGGCCUUUGUUUCUCCGUGGUGAUUACUGCUUGUGCAGCCUCCUGCCAGUGCUAGACCUGUCUGGAAGGGAAGGGCGUGUGCUGUUCCCGUCUGUCUUUGGCCAGAAGAGCCUCCCAUUCUUUGCCUUCACCAUGUUUGUUUUUUUCUGCACAGGAUUUCUCCUGGCUGGGGCACACCCAUUGGUGUUCAGUGGAAGUAGAAACAAUUGGAACAAACAAAAUGUGGAAGCUUAAAGAGAAAAGAAGGAGAUGGUGGGCAGGGCUUCCAGGCCACGUGUGAUCUGUGGCACUGCUUGGCCUGUGGACUGUGGCCACAGUCGCGUUGCUGUCCCUGGCUCCCUUCUCUUUGAAGGUCUCCUUUGCCAGCGCACACGGCUCCCUGGGCUGGAAUGUCUGUUCAUUCAUCCCUGCAGUUGUUUGCGGAUGUCCCGGGGCUAACGUGAGUUAGUUAAUGAAGUCCAAAGCCAAGCCUAAUGGCAAGAAGCCCGCUGCGGAGGAGAGGAAGGCCUACCUGGAGCCUGAGCACACCAAGGCCAGGAUCACCGACUUCCAGUUCAAGGAGCUGGUGGUGCUGCCCCGCGAGAUUGACCUUAACGAGUGGCUGGCCAGCAACACCACGACGUUUUUCCACCACAUCAACCUGCAGUAUAGCACCAUCUCCGAGUUCUGCACAGGAGAGACGUGUCAGACGAUGGCCGUGUGCAACACACAGUACUACUGGUAUGACGAGCGGGGGAAGAAGGUCAAGUGCACGGCCCCACAGUACGUUGACUUCGUCAUGAGCUCCGUGCAGAAGCUGGUGACGGAUGAGGACGUGUUCCCCACAAAAUACGAGAAUUCCCCAGCUCCUUUGAGUCCCUGGUGAGGAAGAUCUGCAGACACCUGUUCCACGUGCUGGCACACAUCUACUGGGCCCACUUCAAGGAGACGCUGGCCCUGGAGCUGCACGGACACUUGAACACGCUCUACGUCCACUUCAUCCUCUUUGCUCGGGAGUUCAACCUGCUGGACCCCAAAGAGACCGCCAUCAUGGACGACCUCACCGAGGUGCUAUGCAGCGGGGCCGGCGGGGUCCACAGUGGGGGCAGUGGGGAUGGGGCCGGCAGCGGGGGCCCGGGAGCACAGAACCACGUGAAGGAGAGAUGAGCCCCCCGGGCCGGACAGGGGCACACGUGUGCAAAGAGACGGUGGUGUGUGUUCUCUCCUGCAUCUGCGUGUGCACACAUGUGCUGGGCACGCGUGUGGUGAGGUCUGAGAGGGCCCCGGGCUGCACUGGUGUGGGCUGCACAGGCACAGACGCAGACGGCCCCGGCCGUGUCCUGUGGCCCCCUGUCGGAUGGAUGCGUGCCGUUUGUAGAGAAGAGCCUUUGGGCCCAUUCACUCGUUCAGCAGACACGCAUGGGACUGAUGCUUUGAGUUUUCUUCUGUGGGGUUUUCCUUUCUCUGGUCUCCGUGCAGCCCCUGCCCUCCCUCGGGUGCUGCUGGCCUCAAAGGAGGAACUCGUGGGGGGAGGGUGUGAUUUGCAGACCUGGGUCUCUGCUCUGCUCUGGGGGUGGGGCUUGCUUUCACAGAGACCCUCCUUCCCUCUCACCCCUCCUCUCCCGGCCUCGCCAGGAGUCUUGGCUGUUGGCAGCUCAGAGGUGGGGGAGGCCUGUGGUGUGAGGUGCCCUGCACCUGCUCCUGCUCCUGUCACCCCUUCCUGCUGCCUCCUCCAUGCCCAAGGAACACCCAUGGUGCAGUCCUCAGGCAAGGCCAGGACGGGGCUGAGGCCCUGCGUGGAGAUGCUGCACCAGCGGAAGGCUGAGACCCGCUUACCUUAGUUCAUCUGUUCACUCGUAAUAAAAAGAAUUCUCUCAGGUCA